GACCCAGCCUGCACCUACUGGCGCCCGAGUUUUAGAGAAUUACUCCAAAUUCAUCAUGAUUGAAGACAAUAAGGAGAACAAAGACCAUUCCUUAGAAAGGGGAAGAGCAAGUCUCAUUUUUUCCUUAAAGAAUGAAGUUGGAGGACUUAUAAAAGCCCUGAAAAUCUUUCAGGAGAAGCAUGUGAAUCUGUUACAUAUCGAGUCCCGAAAAUCAAAAAGAAGAAACUCAGAAUUUGAGAUUUUUGUUGACUGUGACAUCAACAGAGAACAAUUGAAUGAUAUUUUUCAUCUGCUGAAGUCUCAUACCAAUGUUCUCUCUGUGAAUCUACCAGAUAAUUUUACUUUGAAGGAAGAUGGUAUGGAAACUGUUCCUUGGUUUCCAAAGAAGAUUUCUGACCUGGACCAUUGUGCCAACAGAGUUCUGAUGUAUGGAUCUGAACUAGAUGCAGACCAUCCUGGCUUCAAAGACAAUGUCUACCGUAAACGUCGAAAGUAUUUUGCGGACUUGGCUAUGAACUAUAAACAUGGAGACCCCAUUCCAAAGGUUGAAUUCACUGAAGAGGAGAUUAAGACCUGGGGAACCGUAUUCCAAGAGCUCAACAAACUCUACCCAACCCAUGCUUGCAGAGAGUAUCUCAAAAACUUACCUUUGCUUUCUAAAUAUUGUGGAUAUCGGGAGGAUAAUAUCCCACAAUUGGAAGAUGUCUCCAACUUUUUAAAAGAGCGUACAGGUUUUUCCAUCCGUCCUGUGGCUGGUUACUUAUCACCAAGAGAUUUCUUAUCAGGUUUAGCCUUUCGAGUUUUUCACUGCACUCAAUAUGUGAGACACAGUUCAGAUCCCUUCUAUACCCCAGAGCCAGAUACCUGCCAUGAACUCUUAGGUCAUGUCCCGCUUUUGGCUGAACCUAGUUUUGCCCAAUUCUCCCAAGAAAUUGGCUUGGCUUCUCUUGGCGCUUCAGAGGAGGCUGUUCAAAAACUGGCAACGUGCUACUUUUUCACUGUGGAGUUUGGUCUAUGUAAACAAGAUGGACAGCUAAGAGUCUUUGGUGCUGGCUUACUUUCUUCUAUCAGUGAACUCAAACAUGCACUUUCUGGACAUGCCAAAGUAAAGCCCUUUGAUCCCAAGAUUACCUGCAAACAGGAAUGUCUUAUCACAACUUUUCAAGAUGUCUACUUUGUAUCUGAAAGUUUUGAAGAUGCAAAGGAGAAGAUGAGAGAAUUUACCAAAACAAUUAAGCGUCCAUUUGGAGUGAAGUAUAAUCCAUAUACACGGAGUAUUCAGAUCCUGAAAGACACCAAGAGCAUAACCAGUGCCAUGAAUGAGCUGCAGCAUGAUCUCGAUGUUGUCAGUGAUGCCCUUGCUAAGGUCAGCAGGAAGCCGAGUAUCUAACAGUAGCCAGUCAUCCAGGAACAUUUGAGCAUCAAUUCGGAGGUCUGGGCCAUCUCUUGCUUUCCUUGAACACCUGAUCCUGGAGGGACAGCAUCUUCUGGCCAAACAAUAUUAUCGAAUUCCACUACUUAAGGAAUCACUAGUCUUUGAAAAUUUGUACCUGGAUAUUCUAUUUACCACUUAUUUUUUUGUUUAGUUUUAUUUCUUUUUUUUUUUGGUAGCAGCUUUAAUGAGACAAUUUAUAUACCAUACAAGCCACUGACCACCCAUUUUUAAUAGAGAAGUUGUUUGACCCAAUAGAUAGAUCUAAUCUCAGCCUAACUCUAUUUUCCCCAAUCCUCCUUGAGUAAAAUGACCCUUUAGGAUCGCUUAGAAUAACUUGAGGAGUAUUAUGGCGCUGACUCAUAUUGUUACCUAAGAUCCCCUUAUUUCUAAAGUAUCUGUUACUUAUUGCUGAAUUUGUGCCAAGCUCAAUCACAUUCACACUAAAAUUUAACAGGAGACCCUGCUGUCUUUGUUGCUAGCAUGAGCAAAAGUAUAGAGGCCUUUGCACAUGGAGGAUACCUAGUAAAGAGCAAGUAGUCUAGUUUCAAGUGUAGUAUCUUGUAGGGAAAUGGGAGUAGCUAAGCCUGGAAAGGUUGAAUGGGGCAUAAUCAUUAAGACUAGGCUAAAAAUUCGAGACUUUAUUUUUUAGGCAUUAGGGAGCCCCUUCCCAAGUGACUAUCUUCCUUGAAACUUUGUUUUCUUUCAAUGACAUCACACGAUACUGGUUUUAUUCUGGACUAUCUAUCCUACUCAUGGGUCCAAGGGAAACUUAGUAGAGAUGCGACUUGCAUGGGGCUGUACUCAGACAUGUGGUCCUAGGUAUUAUAAUGGGAUUGUCCCCAGAUUAACAGGAAGCAUUGUUAUCAAAGGAAGAGUUCAAACUGAGAUAGAUAAGAGAAGCACAAAGUAAAAGAUAGAAAAAACAGUGCUGAGUACUUUAUUUCUAAGGUAUAAGGUGAGGCCAUAAACAGAAAGGUAUGCAAUGAGAGUAGAGGCUGCAGAAAAGGGGAGGAAAUAGAAUGUCAGAAAGGUCAAGAAGAGUGGUUUAGGACUGAGACUGUAAGUAAUGUAAGGAUUGCCAAGGAAUGGUUUUUAUGCAGAGUCAGCUGUGUAGCACAGGGAGUAAGCAGUCCUGUUAUAAAUGGGUGAAGCUGAACUCCAAAAUACAAACUUAUGUCUCUUUAAUUUGCCCCUUUCCUCCCUCUAGUCACUAAAUGAAGAUGUUCUUCAAGUUUCUGUCUUUGCACUUCUACUCUUUUUGCCAUCUCUUCAUGGGGAAUGUCACCCAGAUACAUGACUUCAGUUCUUAUUUUGAAUGACUCCUCUAUUUGCAGUUAUAACCCUGACAUCUUUCUUGAAUUUUUUUGCCCCUUAAUUCCAACGAACUCCUGGAUGUCUAUGUAGAUGUCUCAUAAUUUAGGCCAAUGCUGUACAACUUCAUGUGGCAUCAUCCACAUAGAAUGAAUAGGGGUUGUUCAAUAUGACAGCCCUGCCAAGCAUCUCAAAUUGAACAGGUCUAUAAAGGAACUCAGAAUCACUUGAAUAUCACAGUCCAUCAGCUUCCUUUCCCAGUAAUUUAAUUUCCAUUAAUGGUAUAUUAAACAUCGUAUUUUCAAUCAUUUUUAGGUUUAGUCAGCUACUUAAAAAUAGGCUUUUUCUUCACAUAAAUAAAUUGUAUACCAUUUAAUGUGUUUUAUUUCAACAGACUAAUAGAUCUUUUAACACUUCUUAGUCCUCAAAAUAAAUUAUUAAAAACUUUGUAUUUCAUGUCAUAUUAUAUAAGGAAAUAGAAUUUUGAAGAAUAAUUCAUGCUGUUUUAAAUUUUUACAUUGUACAUUUUAAUAGCUAAUCAACUCUUAAGUAUACAUUUGAUGGUAAAUAGAUGCUAGCUAAUCUAGAAUCAUUUGAAAUAUUGAUUAUCUGAUUUAUAGUUUGGUUGCAAGGAAAUCUACUGUAAGCAAAUCAUAAUAGAUAGCAAAUCUUAGAACAUGUAGAAAAAAAGAAAUUAAAAAAAGCAAAUCUUAGAACAUGUAGAAAAAGGAAAUUAAAAAAUAGAUAGCAAAUAACACAAAUUAUGCAUACUAUAUGUGGUUAUUUUCAUACAACUUUGAUAACGGUGAAGAAUCAUACUUAUUGAAUUUUAAAAUGAUGAUGUUUAAAAUCACUCUAUGACUAAAGCACAUGAGAAUAAAUGUUAAAGGCACAGCCUUAUAAUCCACAACUUCAGAACAAUGGAAUUUUUUUUUUUUUUUUUUUUUUUUUUUUUUUUUUUUUUUUUUUGAGACGGAGUCUUGCUCUGUCGCCCAGGCUGGAGUGCAGUGGUGCGAUCUUGGCUCACUGCAAGCUCCACCUCCCAGGUUCACGGCAUUCUCCUGCCUCUGUCUCCUGAGUAGCUGGGACUACAGGCGCCCGCCACCACGUCCGGCUCAUUUUUUGUAUUUUUAGUAGAGACAAGGUUUCACCGUGUUAGCCAGGAUGGUUUCAAUCUCCUGACAUUGUGAUCUGCCCACCUCGGCCUCCCAAAGUGCUGGGAUUACAGGCGUGAGCCACUGCACCCGGCCAAACAUUGGAAAUUUUUAAUGAUGGAUUUCAGUUCUUCUCACCUCUGGGUAUUUGUAAUAUUUGGUAAAUCAGGAGUCCUGAGAGUCUUAGAAUUUUCAUGCAUUUUAAAUAUAUGUCUUCAAAGCACCUAGGAAUAUGUAAAUAGUUACCCAAAUGUGAGAACAGAAUUGAACUAAAAGCUUCGUUUAUAAUUUUUUUUUUUUUUUGAGACAGAGUCUCACUCUGUUGCCCAGGCUGGAGCGCAGUUGCGUGAUUUCAGCUCGCUGCAACCUGGGACUGCAGGCGUGCUUCACCAUGCCCCGCUAAUUUUUGUUUUUUUAGUAGAGAUGGGGUUUCGCCAUGUUGGCCAGGCUGGUCUCGAACUUCUGACCGCAGGUGAUCCAUCCGCCUCGGCCUCCCAAAGUGCUGGGAUUACAAGCAUGAGCCACCAUGCCCAGCCGGUUAAUAAUUCUUAAUCAGUAAAUCAUUAUUCAAAGACAUAGUUAAUAUCUUCAUGACUUCUUAAGGAUGCUCAAAAGCUGGUCUUCAGAAUACCUACAUUUCUUUAUCUACAUAUUCUGUCAUUUGGAGUUAUACAAGUAGUAAUGACACACCAAAAUGUAAAUAAUUAUUGUUAGCUUUUAAGUUGGCUUCCAAAUUCAAAAAAGAAAAAAAUCCUGAAUUCUCUAAAGGAACAUAUGAUAGAGUCCAUAUGUUAAUUCAUAGGAAGUGUUUAAGGUACUAUGGUCUAUUUUGGUCUAAUCUUUGUUUUACUAUGUAAUAUAUAUUUAUGAUUUACAAGUUUGUUAUUCAGUGGGAUAAUAAAUGAACACAAAAUUUAUGUUCUCAA